AGGUGCGUACGGCAUCUGACUUGACGUGGCCCACAACUGAAAGGUCUGGGGAGAAGGCGCCGUGUCCGGGUGUGGAGAGGGGCGUCGUGGAAGCGAGAAGAGUGGCCCGUCCCUCUCCUCCCCCUUUCCCUCUUUCGGAAAGUGGUUUCUGCGGGGCCCGGGAGCCUCGGAGUACCGAACCUCGAUCUCCGGGGCGGGGUCCUUGGUGGGGACUGAGCGCCCCCUCCCGGGGACGGGCGGUCUGGCCGCGGAGUCCCCUGCGGGAGCGUGAUUGGCUGGAAACGGUCCCGAACCCCCAGGGGAGCCCGAUCCCUGGGGGACCCUGGCUUCGGACUCCAGUAUCUGUCGUCGCAGGGUCCCUGCCCUAGUGGCCUAUGUCCCUUGCUCGGGGCCAUGGAGACACUGCGGCCAGUACGGCGGCGCCUCUGUCUGAAGAAGGGGAAGUGACCUCCGGCCUCCAGGCUCUGGCCGUGGAGGAUACCGGAGGCCCCUCUGCCUCGGCCGGUAAGGCCGAGGACGAGGGGGAAGGAGGCCGAGAGGAGACCGAGCGUGAGGGGUCCGGGGGCGAGGAGGCGCAGGGAGAAGUCCCCAGCGCUGGGGGAGAAGAGCCUGCCGAGGAGGACUCCGAGGACUGGUGCGUGCCCUGCAGCGACGAGGAGGUGGAGCUGCCUGCGGAUGGGCAGCCCUGGAUGCCCCCGCCCUCCGAAAUCCAGCGGCUCUAUGAACUGCUGGCUGCCCACGGUACUCUGGAGCUGCAAGCCGAGAUCCUGCCCCGCCGGCCUCCCACGCCGGAGGCCCAGAGCGAAGAGGAGAGAUCCGAUGAGGAGCCGGAGGCCAAAGAAGAGGAAGAGGAAAAACCACACAUGCCCACGGAAUUUGAUUUUGAUGAUGAGCCAGUGACACCAAAGGACUCCCUGAUUGACCGGAGACGCACCCCAGGAAGCUCAGCCCGGAGCCAGAAACGGGAGGCCCGCCUGGACAAGGUGCUGUCGGACAUGAAGAGACACAAGAAGCUGGAGGAGCAGAUCCUUCGUACCGGGAGGGACCUCUUCAGCCUGGACUCGGAGGACCCCAGCCCCGCCAGCCCCCCACUCCGAUCCUCCGGGAGUAGUCUCUUCCCUCGGCAGCGGAAAUACUGAUUCCCACUGCUCCUGCCUCUAGGGUGCAGUGUCCGUACCUGCUGGAGCCUGGGCCCUCCUUCCCCAGCCCAGACAUUGAGAAACUUGGGAAGAAGAGAGAAACCUCAAGCUCCCAAACAGCACGUUGCGGGAAAGAGGAAGAGAGAGUGUGAGUGUGUGUGUGUGUUUUUUCUAUUGAACACCUGUAGAGUGUGUGUGUGUGUUUUCUAUUGAACACCUAUAGAGAGAGUGUGUGUGUUUUCUAUUGAACAUCUAUAUAGAGAGAGUGUGUGAGUGUGUGUUUUCUAUUGAACACCUAUUCAGAGACCUGGACUGAAUUUUCUGAGUCUGAAAUAAAAGAUGCAGAGCUAUCAUCUCUUAAAAGGAGGGGCUGUAGCUGUAGCUCAACAGUUAGGCCCCACUUGAAGGGAGAGGCAGAAUUGUACUCACCCAGAUUGGAAAAUGAAAGCCAGAUGGGUAGAGGUGCCCUCAGUUAGCACCUGUCCCAUCUCGGGCCCUCCAACUCCUCCCAGUCCCACUCCAGUGCAGCCAGCUGGCUCCAAGGUAGAAACCCAUGAGCACUCAGGGAGCAGUGUGCCUUCAGCUGCAGCAGAAGCAGCCCGGAGGAUAAAAUGAGAACCAGCUGCACACGGGCCCUUUAACUCCCAAGCCCCACCCCUGGGCUUGGCCUGCCUUGCCCUGCCGGGAAGUGAUCCCCAAGGCAGGGUGAGAGUUCCCCAUCUGAGGCGUUUGUUGCAGCUACCUGCACUUCUAGAUGUGAGUACAUUGUACUAGCCCCCCAAACCCCAAAUCAGGGGCAGAUCUUUGUAUCCCUUGAGGCUCUCUUUAGUCCUGUCUUGCUUUGAAGGGCCUUGCUUCUGCUGGGGCAGGGAAAACAUGUCUGAAUCAGAGUGGGGAAGGAGGAUGGGUGGUGGCUUUGCUUUUGGAGGUUUCACUUUCCAAUAGUUGGGAGUCUUCUGGGUUUUGAAGUAAAGGCAGAUUAACACCAACACCGGUCCCCCACCCCCCUGCAACUCUCAGGCCUCUCUCUGACUUCAGGGUCCCACCUGGGAAAUCAGGUGGGGAACCUUACAGGGUCAUUCAGACCCCAUCUUAGCCCUAGAUCGGUGCUUGCUCUACUCACCUGCACUGUCCUGGGGACCUGGGCUCUGGCCUGUCACCUUGAGCUCCAAGAAUGUGACCUGUACCCAUUCAGGCCCCUUAACUCUGACAGAUGAGGGUUUCUUACUCCUCCAUGCAGGGCUGGGCCAGCUGUUGGUCUCAGUCGAUCAUUCAGGAAGUCAUUAGCAGAGUGAUUUCCAGAAGGCGUAGAAUUUAGUGACCAAGGUUCUUUCCUUUUUGGGAGGAGAAAGUGAAAACUAGGAUGCUCAGCUGGACCCACCAGCCUGAGAUUCUGGGGAUUUUAGAGCUGUCCCUUGGGGAGCCAAGCACUUGGGGGUGGAGGUGAUAGCGAGGCUGAUGGCCCCUGUGUUCUCAGCUCUCUGCCUGGGUAGCCCCUGGGUGAUGGGGGAGAGGCCAGCUGUCACGUGGGGUAUCAGGUGGCUCUGCCAGAAACUCCCUUGGCACACAGAGCACUGGGUCGGCCCUCGGGUGUGGCUGUUUGGGCAGGACAGCCCUCUGUAUGUAGCCUUGAGCAGGUAGGGGGGCCACCUUGAGUGGGUGGCCCAGAGACAGCCUCAGGGCUCCAAGGUAACGGGGUGCUCAGGUUAUCUUGGGUGCUGCCCUCCCAGGUUCUGGGGGAGCAGAGGCUGGGCGCUGGCCCAACUUACAGGAAACACUCACCUUUGAACUGCCAUUAGCACCAUCUGGGCAGUACACAGCCCCACCCAGGUCCUCUAGUUCUUGUUCUCGGCUUAGAAUCUUUGUGUUUCUGCCUGAGAAGCCACUGCCUCCUAGUUUGUGGUCUCUACAGUUAUAGCCAGGUUGGACUUCCGGCUCCGUCCUUUGAUAACUGUGUGCUCUUGGGCAAAUUUCUUAACUUGCAGGUUCUUGUGAGGAUAACAUGAGUUAAUUGAGGGCACUUAACACUACCUGGCACAGAUUAAGCUCAUCUGAAGUGGGAGCUGUUACUUAGGGGCGUUUGCCUAGAACACAGGGUCCAGAGGCUCUCUCCCGGAAACUUAGACCCAGUGAGUCAGAAGUGAGGCCUGCAAAAAGCAGCAGGAGUGGGGUUAAGAAUUCCAGCCUAGGGCUGGAUGCGGUGGCUCAGGCCUGUAAUCCCAGUACUUUGGGAGGCCCGAAUGGGAGGAUGGCUUGAGGCCAGGAGUUCCAGACCAGCCUGAGCAACAUAGCGAGACCCUGUCUCUGUUUGUGUGUGUGUGGUUGGGGUUUUGUUUUUUUUUUUUUUUUAAAGAAUUAUAGCUCAGUCCUAUGAUUAGGCAAGUUGAGAAAAUAUUGAUGAAGAUCAGGGGUGCUGAAGCCUGGUUCCUGGGGUCGCUUCUGAUCUAGGCGGUUCUUGCCUCUGGUGACUGGUGUUAAUUGGCAGGAGUGGGAGGAGGGAGGACAAGUGGAAGUCUAGGCUGGCUGAGCUGUUCUGUCUCGAAAAGUUCCUAAAACUGUGCUGCUUUAAAAAAAAAAAAAGUAAUUUAUGAGACACAUUCUCAAUUUCCAUUAAUCAUCUCCUAAAGGGGGUAAACCAGGAAGCCGCUGGGUGAAAACAGGCUGUUGGCAAUUCCUGAGUCAUGUGACCCAUUCUCUAAAGACUAGAAUAUUUAACUUAAAUCAGUGAGAAACUC